CAGAGUGGGCGGCCCCUCCCCUUUCUCUGAGUGGGCGGGGACAGCGGUUGCAUGGGCAGCUUUCCUUAUGAUGCCACAGGUCCCUCUGGACAUGCUGCUGCCUGGCCACGCCUCCUUUCCCUUUCAUCUUUCUCACUGACCAAUGGGCUUGGAGCAUUAAGGCCACGCCCCUAUUCUGCGUUCCAUUGGUGCCCUGGUUACGCCACCUGUGGCUCAGUUGCACAGCUGCCUGGUAGGUGACUGGAGGCAUUGAGCAGUGCUCACUGGUAUUUCGCUGAUGUGGCCCCAACCCCGCCUCCCUCCCCACCCCGCGAUGUCAGAAAAAACACAACAGGGGAAAUUGGCCGCAGCCAAGAAAAAGUUAAAAGCAUAUUGGCAGAGGAAGAGCCCUGGCAUUCCAGCAGGAGCUAACAGGAAAAAGAAAAUCAAUGGCAGUAGCCCUGACACAGCCACUUCUGGUGGUUACCACUCACCUGGGGAUUCAGCAACAGGUAUCUACGGGGAGGGCCGUGCAUCCUCUACUACCCUGGAGGAUCUGGAGAGCCAGUACCAAGAACUAGCAGUGGCCCUGGAUUCAAGCUCCGCAAUAAUCAGUCAACUCACUGAAAACAUCAAUUCACUGGUUCGCACAUCUAAGGAGGAGAAGAAGCAUGAGAUACAUCUGGUACAGAAGCUUGGGAGGAGCUUGUUCAAACUCAAAAACCAGACGGCUGAACCCCUGGCCCCAGAGCCCCCAGCAGGGCCAUCUAAGGUAGAGCAGCUACAAGAUGAGACCAACCACCUAAGGAAGGAGCUAGAGAGUGUGGGAAGACAGCUCCAGGCUGAGGUGGAAAACAAUCAGAUGUUGAGUCUCCUGAACAGGAGACAGGAGGAGAGGCUACGUGAACAGGAGGAGAGGCUACGUGAACAGGAGGAGAGGCAACGUGAACAGGAGGAUAGGCUACAUGAACAGGAGGAGAGGCUACGUGAACAGGAGGAGAGGCUGUGUGAACAGGAGGAGAGGCUGUGUGAACAGGAGGAGAGGCUACGUGAACAUGAGGAGCAGGAGGAGAGGCUACGUGAACAGGAGGAGAGGCUGUGUGAACAGGAGAAGCUGCCAGGGCAGGAGAGGCUGCUGGAAGAGGUGGAGAAGCUGUUAGAACAGGAGAGGCGGCAGGAGGAGCAGGAGAGGCUGCUGGAGAGGGAGAGGCUGCUGGAAGAGGUGGAGAAGCUGUUAGAACAGGAGAGGCAGCAGGAGGAGCAGGAGAGGCUGCUGGAGAGGGAGAGGCUGCUGGAAGAGGUGGAGAAGCUGUUAGAACAGGAGAGGCGGCAGGAGGAGCAGGAGAGGCUGCUGGAGAGGGAGAGGCUGCUGGACGAGGUGGAGGAGCUCCUGGACGAGGUGGAGGAGCUCCUGGAGCAGGAGAGGCUUCGGCAACAGGAUGAGAGGCUGUGGCAGCAGUAGACUCUGCAGGAGCUGGAGAGGCUGCGGGAGCUGGAGAGGCUGCGGGAGCUGGAGAGGAUGCUGGAGCUGGGGUGGGAAGCCCUGUACGAGCAGCGGGCCGAGCCACGCAGCGGCUUCGAGGAGCUGAACAACGAGAACAAGAGCACACUGCAGUUGGAGCAGCAAGUAAAGGAGCUGAAGAAGUCGGGUGGAGCUGAAGAGCCAAGAGGCUCCGAGUCUGCAGCAGCAGCCAGACCAGUAGCUGGAGCCCCAGUCCCACAAGGAGCUUGGAUGUGCGGACAAGCAGGGUGGACUCCCCAGGAGCACCCAGGCUUGAGUGGAGAAGCUGUUGGUACAGGAGAGGCGGCAGGAGGAGCAGGAGAGGCUGCAUGCCAUUCUUUUCGGGCUGCGGAGAACAGGGAGCUAAACAUCACCAUCAUCUAAGAGCGGGUCAAGGAAUUGAAAAAAAAAAACAAAACAUUUAAGGGGUUAAUAUCCUACACAAUUCAUUUACUUCAUUUGAAUGUUAGAGCCACUUAUGUUUAUUUGUGUUUCUAAUUUAUAGUUUAAAUUUAUUUGUGUUUCUAAUUUAUAGUUUAAAUUUAUUUGUGUUUCUAAUUUAUAGUUUAAAUUUAUUUGUGUUUCUAAUUUAUAAUUUAAAUUUAUUUGUAAAAAGUUAAAUGAGAGUGGGUGUUUCUCUCAUGUUCACUCUGGCAUCUUUUAGCAUUUUUUUAAUUUGAUAAUUAUAGGACGUUAGCAUGCAUAUCGAGUUUGCCCUUAUGUGGUGGGAGUUCAAACACACAAAGACCCACUGUAUGCACACAACUGUUCUUGCUGGUUUGGGAUAGGCUGCCAUGCUUUUUUAAUGUUAGUACAGCCUGUAUAUUCAUUACGGAAUUCAGAUAAAAUUUCCUUAUGUUCUGCUGUUAUGUUUGAUCGAAUCCUAAUCACAGUGAGCUCUUCAUUAGCUCAAUAUGCAGUUUGCCCUCAAGUGCGCGGUCUAUUACUUUGUAAUAUGCCACUGUGAGUACUGACAUUUACAGUUGUUUAAAGGUGGAGCACUGGAAACAGCCUUUCCCCCUUUUUCUGUGUAUUGGGGAUGGGAGUAAUAACAUUUUGGGGAGGUUUUUAAAUCUCCCAGAAGAGGAAAGUGGCCUGCUUUGGCAGGUGUGUGCAGGAUAGAAUAUGUUUCAUUUGUUCCGGUGCCAAGAAUGAGCGCUGUACUACGGUAGUUCCCUUAGGAUUUGUAUGUGCUCUGGGCUCAUGAAGAUACUGCCUCAUGAGCUGUGGCAGUUGUACUCUUUUUUGAUGACCUGAAAAGGGAUUAUUUCUGAGGAAUGAAAGGCUCCCAUCAUGACUGUGGAUGUGGAAAACCUUUUCUAGCUGAGAGCAUUUAUAUCUACAAUACAUUUUAAAGUCAGAGUUCAUGUUCCCUGUUUUAAUCACAUGACUACAUGUCCCAGUACACAAAAGGGCACUGGUUGGCGUUCUCCUUAAUGUAUUUAGUAAAGAUCAGAAGAAAUCCUUUAAGAGUUUAAAUGCCCCUGGAACAGGCAUAUACAGGCUCUAGUCAAGAAUGAAUUCGAGUGAAGGAAAGCUGUGUGACACCUGGCAUUCCUCUGUGUUCAUGGAGCUUAUUUGAGGCUAGAAGAUGGAUUUUACCAUCUAGACCUCUCUGGCUAAUAGCUAGUCUUCAACCAUCUGACAUAGGAAUUUACUUCUUUUCCUUGAAUGGAGAACACUUUAAAAAUAAUAACAAACAUUAUUAUAAACUAAUAUAUGUGAGAGUACUUAGUUGAAACAAAAAGGAGUUUUAGUAGACAGUAUUAUACUACAUUUGAAAAUCAAGGAGCAGUUUAUGCAACGUAAAAUGUUUACAAACUGCAGCGCAAUCUACUGUUUGUGACUGUCAAAGUGUCAUGAGGAAAGUGUCUAUACAAUCACAGAGUUAUAUUUCCUCACAAAGUUCUUUACGAAGAGUGAAAUAUGUUUUUAUACCUCUCAGUUUCAGUUAGAGGCAUAUUUUGUGUAAUAUUUAUGGCUUAAAAUGGACUAAAGGUCCUGUUCUUGCCUUUUCUGAACUUGCCGCUUUUGCAUUCUUUGAGUUCAGUUUAAAGACACUUACUUUAACUCCAUUUUAAACCCUCGGGCUAGAAAUCGUACCACUGUUAAUUAGCCACGUUAUUUGGUCUAACAGUUUUUGUUUAUCAUUCUGAAACUGAGCUUAUCUAAUACAUUGAUAAAUUAUUUCAAAGGUAUUUUUAUAGUUCAAAUCGCUUCACUUUUACCCUGACACGUAUAAAUGAAUAGGAAUGACCUUCAGAUAGCGUUUAGCAACUGUAACCAAUCUGACAAUAAUGUGUUCAUCAGGUACCUGUGGAUUAAAUCACAUACUGGCAUAUUUAAGAUGAAUGUCAGUCUGAAAAAUAAAUAUACUAUAUUAAUUCAAAUACGACUCUUUGUGUAGGUAUUUUGUCAUAUGUUUAAGAAAAAGCUAAAGAGAAUGGAAAUCCUAUGACAAUAACUCAAGUCUUUCUUCAAAGUGCAUGCAGUCUUUUGCAGUACCUCAUUCAGCCAAGUAUUUGUUCUCUACCUCAUUCAGUAUAAGGCAGCCUUUAAUUUGCUUAGAAGGCAACAUUAGAAGGUUAGAGUUCAGCAGGAACAUAGAAUUUUAAAAUGUGACUUCAACUGAAUAAAUUUGAAUUUCUGUAGGGAGUAAAGAAUCAAAACACCUAUUUAAAGACUGCAAAAUAUGAUAAUUAUUUUUAAAGUAAUUGAUUAAACCUGGUAGGUUUUCCCAAAAUGAAAAACAAUCAGUUCUAAAACCAAAGCUGAUUUUUAGAAAAUGUGAAAAUGUAAAUCAACCCUAUCCAUAAUAGAUUCUCUAAAACUUUAUCUUACAGUCACUUUCAAAUAACUAUUCAAAAAUGUAACUGCUAUAUUAACGUCUUAAAAUAAUUUAAAACAUUUUAAAAUAUGAAUACUGUAGUUUAAAACAAAGAAUCUAGGGGAAGGAAAAGUAGACAAAGAAAUGCCAAUUCCAGUCCAAAGCUGUAUUUGCCAAGUUUUCUUAGAAUGACUUUUACCGAUUUAUGAAUUCUUAUACACAGAAUGCAUAAUGGAAAUACUGAUUUUUGUCUAAAGUGGCAUUAUUGACUGCUGCUGUGAUGCUACUGUAAUGUAAUACAUUAUUAAAUUGUUUCAAGGUGC